AAAAACUCUCUCCAAGUGUAACUCUCCAUUGAUAAAUUCCCCUCAUUUCCUCAUUUCCCUCUCCUGCCAGCACCCGGUUAACUCUCUAAUAAAAAUUGACCAGAUUUAAAAAACUCCAUUUAGUGGUUCCUGCGUAAAGAGAUGGUAUUUUGGUCACUUUAAUUUGCAUGAGAUGUUAUCUGAAAUCGACCACUAAUUCUUCCUUCUCACAGCCCCCCAUCCCAUUCCUCUCUUUACAAACCGCGUAACUACAUACUAUCCAGGACAAUAUAAAAGUGACCUCAAUACUCCUAUUGCAAUCAAUGAAAUAUGGUGAACAGUACAGGUUUGUCUUUCAUUGCUCCCUGCCUUGAAAGGUGUGGGUAGAGGAAGAAAAAUCUCCCUUACAAACUAUUUCUCCAGUUACAAGUCUUUGUCCAGAAGCAAAAGAAGGUUUUAACGUUACAGUACUUAUUCUAAUAGAAUUUUAAUUGCCCUAAUCCUGCUAAAGUGUGAAGCUGAGUGUGUGUGUGUGUGUGUGUGUGUCUGUGCAUGUAUUCCUAAUAGGGAGGGGAGUCAUGCAAAAAAAAAAAAUCUUUGUUACAUUUUUCAUGGGUGGGGCAGGGGGUGUCACAUAUGUUAAAUGAUGCAAACUUAAUUAAACUGAUUCUGGGGAAGGACAGGCCAUUGGCGUUCCAUCUAUGAAAUGUGUACUCCACUUUCGGUGGGAACAGAGUGGUCUUCUGUGUGCUUUGGGAAUUUCUAUUUUUGAAAGUGAAGUGCUUGGUUCCAGUUGCAAACAUGCCCUAAACCCUACUUGUCAUGACUGAGCUAGACAUGCUGGCAAAUUAUAUAGAUUGAUCCUACACAAUAACCUCCAAAAUGGCACUUGGUAACUAUACCAUCCUGCUAACUGUUUGAGGCACAAUAGUUUUGUAAUAUAAUAUAAAGUAAUGGUGUUAGCCAACACAUCUUUAAUAAGAUAUUGUUCGUGCCUUUGCCAUAUGCUACAGAGCAGCCUCUCACUCGGUGGGCCUUUUGAUUCCUCUCAAUAAGAUUAUUUCAAAUACUCUAAUCCUGAAUCAUUGACAUGAAUACAAAAGCCUAGUGACAUCUAAUAGAUGCCUCUUAGCUUUGCUUUUCCUCUUGUUCCUUUCCUUUUUCUUCUCUUUUUACCUGACAAAAAGCUCAUAGACACUUGGGCUCUGUCUCUCAGUAGCAGCAUGGGGGGCUCCUCAUGAAAUAUAAAGGGGGAAAAAGGACUGACAGAGGCCCGAUAAGCUACAGAGUGAAGGGCCAUAGAUUAAAAGUAAAUGCCAGUAAAUCCUACCCUGUACACUCACUUGUUCUUUUAUUGUUUUCUUUAACACUUUCAGAGCCAGGGCAGGGAAAAAACCAGAAAAUAGUAAUCAAGCUGCCCAUGUACAUUUUUAAUCUGGACACUGUCACUAUUAUACAUAUUUUAUGGGGCUUUGGCGACAUUCUCAAAUUUUGGUUCAUGUAAAGGUUGUGGUGGGUUUUUUUUUUAAUGUCCUUUUAAUCAAUAUCAAGAAUCCCUCAAGAACUUUUUUGCUCAUUUGCUGCUCAAUUAACUUAAUAUUGAUACCAUGUGUGGGUAGGAAGAGCCCUUCUGUAGGGUGUGAACACUGGGGCUCAGGACAUGACAUCUUCAAGGCUGAAAUAACUUUUUUUCUUUUCUUUUUUAAUUGAUGAAUUGAAAAUUAUCAAAGUAAAAUGAUAGGGUAUUUUGUUUCAUGACAUCAGCUGCUGCUUUUUGAUGUGGUGCUGCUCCCCGCCAGUGCCGUGAAUUCUCCGCCUUUGCCGGGUGGUGCACGCGACUUAGACUCUGCUGGUGCAUGCCGAGGAGUCAGGAGCCCAGCUGGGUAACUUUUCUAAUGGUCAAAAGGUUGUUCCCUCCUCCACCUUCCUGAAGCAACCAUGAUUUGACUAAAGCUCUUUAUUACUCCACCUGAAUAUCAGACAGUCAUGCUGCUUGCAAUUUAUUUAUUGUUUUCCAGAGGUAAACUACUGAGAUUUUCCCCACCUGUUUUUAAUGUGCUUCUCGUUCAUAAGUAUUCUGAUCUGUUAGUAAUAUCUGAAAAUAUCACUUUUAACACUCUUGGGUGCACUAUUGGCUGAAGCCCCCUCACAGAAUGGAAAGUUAAUUUGAAGAACUAUGGACCUGCAUCAGGUUUAGCUACACACACCACACACAUACGCACAUACACACACGCACAUACUCUACAGAGACCAAAAAAAAAAAAAAAAAAAAAAAAAGAUGAAAAGAGAGCAGUCUCUUUUUCAUUUUUUAAAAAGUUCUUUAGAAAAGAAAGUUGGUUAAGGGUUCACCUGGUUAUCUUUGAAGCUGUUACCAACAGUUGAAAACCCAUGUUUCUCUACACAGUCUUGUUGUUUUCCUAAAGCCAGAUUCUAAUGUUAGAUAUAUGGGAUAUGUCUCAGAAUAUGGUUUUAAACACUGAGUUGUUCUUCCUGUAGCUGUAGAAAUGGGAGUGCCCUGAUCUGGCUCGUGAAGACCAGCAUCUGAAUCCUGGUCUAUGAGCACCUUAAAACAAAGCAAGCAAAACCCCUGAUCACUGUGAGUUUAAUAGUAGCUUACACCUAAAUGGCACUUCCAGCGUUUUAGAGCACGUCGGGGUAUACCAUCUCAGAAAAUUCUCUUUGCACAAAUUGACUCCAUUUGACAGAUCUGUAAACUGAGGCACACAGCCUAAGGAACUAUCCACUUUAUUGGUGACAAAGCAAGUGAUUAGAAACUCCACAUCUCCUAUCUCCCAGACUGAUUUUUUUCCCUUUUCUCAAUUGCUCAGCUAAAAACACUGUUUUCAGUAUUUCAUAAUGUCUCUUUUAUUUCAUUUUUCUUGCUAUCCACAGCACAUUUUCAUGUAUUACUCUAAACCUAUUUACCAAGCCAGCUUUCUUAGUUGAUGUCACAAUUAACUUUCAGGAUUUUAUAUGUAUAUAUACACACACAUAUAUAUAAACACAUAUAUAUACACACACAUAUAUGCAUAUAUACAUAUGUGACACUGUUUAUUGUACUCAUUGCUGGAGCAAUGUUUGAGUUCUUAUGUCCUCAUUUAAUUUGAUUGUGUAUUUGCUUGAAAAAAACAUCAGUAAUCCAUACAGAAAUCUGGGAGAAGGCACAGUAUGAUGGCAAAGGCAUAGAUUUUGGAGUGCAUUGGCUAAGGGAUCCAGUUCCUCCACAGCUACUUAUUAGUAGCUGAGCCUCAGGGGGCUCAGUUUUCUCAUCUUCAAAAUGGGAAAAGUCACUUCUAUUUUGAAGCGUUGUGAGGAUUGAAACACCUAGCACUGGGCUUGGCACAUAACAGGUGCUUAAAAUCAGGUAGCUCUUGCAAUUUGAGCAUCGUAUAUUCCAUGUGGAUUUUCAUUCUUAAUGUGAUCAUUGCCAUGGGACUUCCUUUGAGCACAAUUACCUUACUGAAGUUAAUCAUGGUAGCUAAGUCUCCUUAGAUAAAGACUCAUUCAUUGUUUUGUUUCCACAAAUAUUUAUUAAGCCUCUAUUAUAUGUCAUGCACUGUUUUCAGGGUUGGGGGUAUAACAGUGAAAAAGACAAACAUAGUUCCUGGCUUCAUGCAGCUUUCUCAGUGUCUCAGGGUUGAUCUCUGCCCCCAGUCCCCCAAAAAUAGUUGGAAUAGUAAUAGCAAGUAUAAACAAAGAAUAUAUUGAUAUAUAUGUUUUAAAAAUAGAAGAAUGCCAUUUUACACUGGGAUCAUGAUGCAGAAGAAAAAUAUCCCCGGGUUAAAGUCACCUUUUAGCUCAUACCCAGAGGUAUCGAACUUGGGCAAAUUCCACGGCUUUAUUGCACUCUUCUGAGGCAGUCUACAUGUUGGUUAAGACUGAAGGAAGAGAUCUCUAAGACCCUUUCCAACUAUGGAAUUCUAAUUUUAGCUGUUUGUGGUAUUGCUGAGCACAGGCAGGUAGAUGAGCGCUUUGGAGGGUAGGUUGUAAGCCUAAGAGGGCAGUGACUACGUUGAGCACAGUGCCUCCCUCCUGUGUACUAGAUGCUUAGGGCUUGUUUUUGUGAAAAGAAGGAAUGACAGGAACUAGAAAUGCAGUUGUUGAAUCUGGUGGUCUCAUCUCUCUGUCUAAAGACAAGCUUGUUAUAACUACACAAUAAAGUGAAAUGGCACUGCCAUUAAAGAAUGAUGAGGAACAGAAAAUGUAAGAUAAAAUAUUAAAUUUGUUACACUUAAAAAUGUUAAUCUUCACACGAUUACCAUGCAAAUCUCCUCAUUGCCUAACUGUUUAAUUGAUCAAGUAAAUCACAGAGCAGACAAGUGAAAAUCUCUGCUGUUGACAUUCUCACAAAGCAUAUUUUCAAGAAUAUAUUCUAUUAACUAUGUGUAUUACACAUGAUAAUGGGAAUUUCUUAUUUUGUAAAAACAUAUAUAUGUGGCAUCCUUUGCAAACCACCAGAUUUCAGAGAGUUUGGGAGAAGGCUUGAUUUUUGCAGGGCAAAAAUUCAGCCAUCCUCUAUUAUGUCAAACGCGAAAUCAGUGUUAGAAAGACCCCUGUGCAAGCAGCGCCUUUGUUUUAUAUACUAUUAGAAGACUUCAGAAUUCACCAGUUUUUCUUUCAGGCAGGUAUAGCAUUGACCUGAUACUCUGGAGAUUGAAGGGUUAAUGAAUUCUCUUUCCCUCCCUCCCCCUCCCCAAUCUUCCUGUCCCCCACCCCCAAUCCCAUCAUGUGCCUGGUUGACUCUGAAAGAAGGGGCUUGAAGUUACCCACAGGGCAUCCCUUUCCCCAGCCUUCUCCAAGGCCACCUGGGCAGACGGGAGCUUGCCUUCUGUCCUUAGGACACAAAAUCCAAUCAGGCGCCUGGCCUGCUAGUCUCUCUGACCUGCGAGCUGGGAAGAGGGAGGAGAAGCAGAGGCCCUCACAUUUGAUAGGCUGCAUCUUUGUGGCUUUAGGGGGCUCCUGUGUCUACUCGAGGAAGGAAGUUCUCCCUUAUUUUAAGAUAAGGUGUCAUUCAUGAGAGCAAUGUGCUGAACUAAUCAGGUUAAUUGAGAGGCCGUGAGUCGUCCUCAUUGAGCCCAUCUCUUCUUCCUGUUAAAGGCAGAUAGCGCAGACAGACAGAUUACACAUAUUUUAGUUUUUUCCCAAAAGCUUAUGAAAUAAUGUAGGCAGGCAGGGAACGUAGGUUCAGCUGAAUGUCAUUCAGGCUAUUUGAACAUGGAUUCUUAUUGUAGAACAAUGUAGCAUUCAAAAAAUAAUAAAAGAAUAAGCUCUCCUCAAGAUUGAAAGAUGAGUGUCUCUGAAUGUCUGAUACACUCUUUUUUUUCUUAAUAUUAUAUUAAACUAACCUCAGCAUUUCAGAUCAACUAGGAAAGAAUGUUUGUUGAAGAGUCCAGUUAGAUUCCUCCGCGGCUAUUUUAUUUAGGAUUGAAACGUAAAAAAAAAAAAAACAAAACAAUCUCAUUGUGAUGUGUCAUCAGUGACAAGUAGCUUCUUGAGCCAUGUUUCGAUUCUUCGGCUUCCGAGCCGGACACUGGGGGCCGUCGCCCUGACUAAUCGCAUCUCGGACCUCCCUCUGGAGCAGCCGAGUGGGGAAGAAAACAGAGCUGUUUCAACUGAAUUCCAUAAAGGGCGGGGGCUCCUCCUCCCUCUUCUCCACUCAAAAUGAUUUGUCAUAGUUUAAUUUUAAACACUAUCAUUGACUAUUCUUUCUUUCUACCCCACCUCUUUCCACCUUUUUUUUUUUCUUGGAAGUUCCAGGAAUGACUUUAAUUAUCUCCACAAUCAAAUUCUCGUUGCUGCCUCUGUGAAAGUGUGCAGUCAUAGAUGGCAGGGAUUAUUUUCUUUAGCACUUGGGGAUACAGAAACCGGUUGUUUCAAAAUGAGAACCAGCUGGUUCCACAGAGCCCUUAUUUAAUGGGGAGCCACUUUGUACACAAAGCCUUUGCUCAGGUCAGUCAUUAUGGCAAACCCCAAAUCAGCAGUGUUUUGUCUAUCACCCUGUAUUAAAUGUCGAGCGAGGAGUGAUUUAGCAGAUAUGAUAAUAAUAAUAAUAAUAAUUAAGAAAUACCCAGCACACCCUGCAUCUUUAAUUUUGCCUCAACUAAACACUCCGGUUUGGAAGGAACAUUUCUCAAACUUCUUCCUACAGUGAUUACAAUCAUAGACCUAGUUUACCACUGCUCUCUCAUAGAUGGCUGAGGGGUAUGUGUGUGUGUGUGUGUGUGUGUGUGUGUGUGUGUGUGUAUGUAGCUUUAACCCUCUCUAAAUCUAGAAAAUAAAAUUAAGCUCAUCUUUCAACAUAAUCUUUUAUCUGACAAGCACAGUAGAUAGAUGAAAGGUAGAUAGCCAAGUUGUGGGUCCCCUUAAUAGAACCAAUUGGAGGGCAGAGAUAACUGCUAUUAUCAAACAUCUUUUAUGCCAUCCUGUAAAAUAAGGACGAGGGUGAUAUACCAUAUAUAUUUUGCUGUCUUUCUAGCUUGUAGAAAUUGGUUUGUUGUCAUACCCUGUUAAUCUCUAACAGCACUAAAUUCAAUUUGAAAUGAGGAGAGUACUUUCACUAUUUGACUGUACAAAAUACUUUUGAAGCAUGCAAAAAGAAAAAAAAAGGAUAAAAGACACGUAAAACCACAAUAGAUAUUCGGUUAUGAGAAUAGUUUGUUUUUAGAACCUAGGUUGCAUUUUUCUAAGGUGAAUAGUUUUGGAGGAUGCAGUAUUUAUUCAAUCAGGAAUUGAAGAAUUAAAAAAUAGCAACUUUACAUAGAUUUUUAAAAAUCUAGUUUAACCAAAUUUUAUCUUUCAAAUAUGAGAAAUUAUUUUGCAUUACUAAUAAGAAUAUGUGGCUUUUAAAAAUUAUGACAUGCUUUUUUUACAUUGAUAGCAACACAACAAAAUACUUUGAAGAAAGGAUAACGAUUUAAAAAUUUAUUCUCACAGGGAGUUUCAUUAAGCUGAGCACUGGUAUAUAUGUUUUUAAUUAUUUUUAUUUUUAGGAUUUCCAUAUUGAAGUAUGGUUUGGGUAAAAUCUUAUCAAAUUAUUUUGUUUGUUUACUAAGUACUUUGAUUGUAUAAUGUCUCUAGUUCAAACUGUAAUUCUAUUUUAUAUUUUCUGUAUUUGUAUUUUUAAAAAAUUCUGUUGAUUUUUUAAUAUAAAAAACAAAUGACUGUUAUAUUUCUAGUCACUCAAAUUUGAACUGAAUUUUACUUCCUGUUUCAAAGGUCAAGGCAGGCUGACCUCAACAGCAGUGUGGAGGCUGCUGAAUUAUUCAUAUCAUUGACUUUGUGUCAGCUUCCACAUUUGUGGAGAGGGAUGUUUUAUUCAUUUAUCUCAUUUAGGGUUCUUCUCUGCACCUGUUUCUACCAUUAAGUACCCUGUAAUUUGCAUUUGAUGCUAAUUUAGUUUCAUAUCAGCCUGGUCCCCCCUUGUUAAUUUAAUUUUCUAAGACCCUUUUCAUUACAGUAGAACUGUUUUCCUCUUUAAAGCAAACAUCUAUACAAGUAAUUGUAUAAACUGCCUUUUAAAUAAUAUCUUUUAGAAGAUUCCAUCGUUUAAUUCCUUAAUUCCUAUAAUUAGCCAUGGUUUGAUUAAUGUUUCAAAGGGUUAAAUUAAAAUGCAGAAUUACUCAAAUGCAUACUGGAAUAAUUUCUUAUAUACAGCAGAGUUAGCGUUGUGGUGUUCUUCCUGAGAAUUCUCAGACAGUAUGUCUUAACAGCAGUCAUUUUCUUUAUUUAGAGUGCUGUUUAGUUUACUAAUAGUGAUUCUUUCAAAAUCACUGUGCACUCAACAUUACUCGUGAAAUGUUAGUUUUUUUUUUUUCAUCAAAUUGUUGAUAGACAGUGGCUUAAAAAUGUUUCUGCAACAUUGAUAAUGACAUACCCAAAAUAAUCAGGGCAGAAUUAGGUCCAAUUCCUUGAUCUAUCCUGGAAGUUUGGUAUAAUGAAUUUCAGGAAACUCUGUUAUAUUAUAUGUCUGUUUCUCUUCUUACCAGCUCUUUUAUUUCUGUCUGCUGCUCAGGGUAGAUUGCCUGGAAAUUUGUCAGCUUUCCAGACAUGGUUUUAGCCAGCUUUGGUUUGUAUCUACGGACACCCGUUGGGCUACAGUUGCCACCUACAUAUUGUAGAAAUUAGGAGUAAGUUGUUUGAGGAGGCCUGAUUGAAAUGGUGGCUACAUGGCAGAAGUGGCCAUGUCCCUGGAAUGUCUGUCAAGGAUUUGGGGGUUAUGAGAACAUGCUACUCAUAUAAACCAGGUCCAUAGCCCCUCUGACUGUUCAGAAAAGAAUUCUAGCUCAGUCCUUUUCUUGGAACUGUUUGGAGGGUGUUUGACAUGAAUGGCCUUAUGGAAUCUGUUGGUAGUGGGAAUUCAAAACAAGGGUAUGAAUUACGAAUUCAAGCACUAAGAUACGUGAAAAUUAAACAGAAGGGAAGUGGCUGCAGCUGAAUAUUACUAAGAAAUUAGCCCAAACUCUACAGAUCCUUCUUCCACUAGGUUGGAUUAGUUUGAUCUGUUGUUCAUAUUCUCUGGGAAAACCAAAUGAGGCAGUUCCUUUGGGUUUCCGGAAAGAUCUCAGGUCUAUUGGAACUGGAGUUUGAAGGUGGCUUUUCCUUUUCUUUCAGUUAUAAAUGAUUCCUGGGGACUCCCACACACAACUUUGUCAUUGUGGAAAUGUGAAAGGGUAUCUCCAGAUUUUCUAGCAGACAGCUUCAUUUGUCUGGUUGCAAGGUAGGGCUGGGGGUGGACUGGACAAUUCCCCAGGGUCCCCUUCAGCUGAGAACUUCCCUGGACCUACCAGUGACUUUUUCACGUCCUACAGCUUAUUAAGCUAGCUCUGUGCUUCUGCUGAUGGUCCUAAAGCAAAGUGAGAGCUUUCAGGAAUGAAAUACAGGAUCUUUAUUCAUUAACAAAACAUUUUCUUACUCAUUCUCCCUCCUACAUCCCCCUCCUCCAGGUUUAGAUAUUCUUUUUAGUUUGGACAAGUCUGUAAGCUCCAAUAGAAAAGCCUCCUUGAGGUCUGAUUAAACGGCUGGGUUUAAAAACAAUAAAGACUAUCUGCAGAGCUCAUGAGAAUGCAGGAAAGGUUUUCCCACCCAAUUCUGGCUGAUGCUUGGAAUUCCACUGUCAGAAUCUCAUCCCUUUAGCUAAGAACCUUCAAUGUAUACCAAGACAUACAAAACUUAGGGAAGGCUAGCACUUUAAUUCUAUCAUUCACAUACCUCUUCGAGGGAAUGACAUAAAGAUCUCACAUGGGUUCAGCUCUUUUUAGUUUUCAUGACAACACAGUGAGGUAAGCAGGAUUUUUUUGUAUCAUUUCACAAAUAUGGAGAAUGAAUAGCUUAAGAACGCUAAUACAUAGCCUAGCUAGAUCCCAAAGGCAGGUUUUCCAAAAAAUCUAGAUUCCUGUAGGAAGAGACCACGAUUCCAUUUAAGCUGAGUGGACUCUCAGAGAUUACAGUUCAGCCCCUUCAUUUUAAAGAUGAGAAAGCUGAGGCCAAGAGAAGCACAGCAAUGUUGCCCAAAGACCUAAUUAGUCUCAGAGCCAGGACCAUAAGCCAAGUCCCUGGCUCUGGUUCCAGUGGCUUUUCUACUACUACUCUGGGCCAUCUGGGUCCUGCUCUGCUCUCCAUUUCACCUUGUGUGCAAUCAGCCUUAGGGAAGGGUACAACGUGUCUUUUCUGGGUUUGGGUCCAAGGAAGCCCCUAAGUCCUGUAUCUCUAACAAGGCCUAGCAUUGUGCACGGAGCACAAGUUAAAUUGUUUCUCAGAAAUUAUAACAGUCCGUCAGGCGCGGUGGCUCAUGCUUAGUAAUCCCAGCACUUUUGGAGGCUGAGGCAGGUGGAUCACCUGAGAUUAGGAGUUCGAGACCAGCCUGGCCAAAAUGGCAAAACCUCGUCUCUACUAAAAAUACAAAAAUGAGCUUGGUAUGAUGGCACAUGCCUGUAAUCUCAGCUACUCAGGAGGCUGAGGCAGGAGAAUCACUUGAACCCAGGAGGCGGAGGUUGCAGUGAGCCAAGAUGGUGCCAUUGCACUUCAGCCUGGGUGACAGAGUGAGACUCCAUCUCAAAAAAAAAAAAAAAAAAAAGAAAAGAAAAGAAAAGAAAGAAAUUAUAACAGUCACAGGGAGGAGGAAGCUACAGAAUAUCCCAUCAUAAAAUAUUACUUUAUUUUUAAAAGCCCACAUAUUUCAUUUAUUUGCAACUGUGCUUGUUCAUACUAUGUCAUAUAACACCGUGCGACAAAUUGCAAUUUUUGUUUUUGUUUGCCAGAGGUAUUUCAUCAAUAGUCAUCUUUCAGUAGGAAUUUUACAAAAGGUCUUUCUAUUCCAGAUGUCUUACCAUGAGCAGUUGUCUCUGACUAUUAUCUUUCUCUGGAAGGUACUGACAUACAUAAAUAUUGACGUUGGCAAUUUUCAAAGUAAGUCUUAAUAAAAUUUUUCUUUUAUUUAAACCUAAACAAAUUGAAAGUACCCUUUCCAAAAAUAAUAAUAAAGGAAGUGAGGCAUUGUUGCAGAAUAUAAUUCUGAAAAAAUUGUAGUGAAAGGGGAAAAAAGUACACUGUAUUUCUUCCUACUCAAACCACUUUUGUGUACAGUUUUGCCUAAGCCCGAAGAGGUUUGUCACACAUUUGGAAUUGCCAAGGAAGGGCAGAAGUCAUGGGUAUGGUGCUGAGAGAAAUUAUUAGCCCCUGGCAUAGUCUCAUGCUGAACUGCAGGAGAAUGAUUCCAGAAGGCAAAGGGGCAUUCAUUCGCCUGGUAAGCUAGAGGGAGAGGUGGGGAGUUGGCAGCUUCUGUACUGUUUCAGAGUAUGGGGCAAAGGAGGAAGUGACAAUUAUUUCACCUCUGAAUUAUUUGACUAUCUGGUCUGGCUGAAAAGAUUGUGCUGAUUUGGAAAAAUUUAAUUUUUUCCGUCUCCACAGAAAUAUAUGACUGAAUGUAGUCAACCAACUAAAUCUUUCUUCCCAGUAUCAAUCCACUAAAAUUAAUUUUAAAAGGUGGAAUUUUGAAUUUAUGUAUACUCUUUUCUUCUCUUUUUCUCUUCCCAAAUUGUCAUAAAUCAUUCAACAGGCUGGAUUCCUUUCUGCUCCCAAAUAGUUUGAUACCAGAAGCCAGAAAGGAUAAUCAUGCUAAACCUAUUAAAAAAUGGUUUCAUGUAGGGUUAGUCUCUCCUUUAGAAACCAUUGUUUACAUUCACAGAGGUGGUGAGGACAAGCAGCUGUUGAGUUCAUUGACCUCAGACAGGAGAAACAAAGGACCCAGCAUGUUAAUUUAUUCAAUAAAUGUUCGUGAAGCAUCUACUAUAUAAAAUAAGUUGUACCCCCAAUCCCAGAUUGGGGACUGCCCCAGAAGCACUUUGUGGUCCUCCCAGGGCACUCACCUAUUAAGGAAAUUGGAUUUGGUGUAGAAUCUCUUUCUCUUUUCCAAAUCACCACCAAAUCCAUUGCCAUUCAUCUUUCUCCUGCCAUUACCUGGCCAUUCCCAGGGUAAGGUCCCACCUCCAAAAAGAGAUUUAAAGUAAUUCACUACUCAUCAGAUUUAGUGUAGGUUAAUUCCCUACUAUGCUAAUAAUUUUCAUCUUCAAGGUACUAAUAGUUCUAAUAUGAACCCAAAUUUGUGCAUAUUCUUCUGUUAAGGAGAAAGCAUGCUUUGGUUCUGUUAAAGGCUCGACACAUUAAAUUGCUCAUUCUGAUAUGGGACUUCUCAUUCAUUAUGAAAUGAGAAGGAACCUCAUGUAGAAUGCUGAACUGGGACACAGGAGACCUGGUUUUGAGUACUGCCCCUGCUGUUAUUUAGAUAUGUGAGCCUCUGUGUCUGUGUGUCUCUUAACUUCUCUGGAUUUCAGCUUUCUUAUUUAUAGAACGAGAGAAGUAAACACUUAGGAUCUUUAAGGUUACCUCUCUCAAUGACUUUAAUCCUCUCUACCCUUAUAAAUCUGGUUACCUCUCAUAUCUGACAUUGGACAGUACCUAUUAUUAAACAUGUGCUUAAGUAGCAUGUACUAUAAGGUAAAUAGCAACCUCACAGAGGUCAGAACUGAAUAACCAACAAUAUUCUCAAUCAACUUUCAGUUCUUCUUCCUUACCUCAUCCAAGGGAUCAGCCAGGUAAUAAGAAGAUAAGGCAGCAGGUACAGCCCAUGUCUAUUGCUAAAAUCUACCUUAAGGCAGGAAGCUAGUGGGUGAGAUCUUUAGAUGAUGCACCUUACAAGGCUAAUUGAGUUGUUAUAUUUAAAUUUAUUGGUAGCAUAACUUGGGCAAGAUGGGGAAGGGAUCUAGUAAAAAGAAAAUUGUAGGCUUGUAAAAUGUGAGGCACGUGGACCAACACAUUUGUCUCUGUGAGAUAGUAACCCCAAAAGGUUGUGGGCAGAGGUUGCCUGUGCAACAUCCUCAAGUUGUCUCUUAAUCUGGUUGAGACUUGUCUUCCAGAUGAAGCAGCCUAAUGUUGAUAUACAGAGAAUCUACACUAAGUUGCACAUAGUACAUGCUCAUUAAAUAAUUGUUCAUUUUCUGCAUAUCCACUUUGUUUCUGUACUUUUAGGGUGUAUAAUUCCUUUUAAGGCAAAUAAUGCUGAGCAUCUUUGGAAUGAAGCUAUGAAAUUAUAUGCUCUGCUAAUAUCCUUUGCUUGUGAGUGACAAUACAGUAUAUAUUCCUUAAGCUUGAAGAAAUUGGAAUUUCAUAAAAUCUUGAAAAAAAUUUUUUUCUAUGUGCAGAGGAGACGAGAGAGAGACUGAGAAACAGAAAACUUUGUCCAGGAUGGGAACCAGAUCUCUCUCUCUAUUUUUUAAAUUUUAAAUUAUCCAACCGUUAAAUAUAAACAUUAUAAUAUUUUGACAGGUUUCCAAAGAAAUAAAAUUGUGAGUCCCAUGGAUAAUGAUUUUUCUGAGAAUUCCAGGUACAGAAUAGGCCCUUUCAGGAUUUCCUGUUUUUUUGUUUGCUUUCCUUCGCUUCUUAUUUUAGGUCCAAUAAACCUUUUACUUUAAGCAGGAUCAAGUGUUAAGACAAACCAACUACAGAGCUAAUGUAUAGAACAUUAAUUCUAUAGAAAUGCCCUAUAAAAAGCAAAGAAAUAAGACUAACUAUUAAAAGAAAUCCAUAUGUCUCUGGAAUUUUUAUUUAAGUUUAUAUUAGCAAUAAUGACCUUGGUUCUAGGGAAUUCGGUAACGAUUAAUGACCAGCAAGGGGUCACUGGCCUCAUGGUGCUUUGGGCCAGCAACCCCUUCCAAAGAGGACAAGAACUGGCCAUUUAUCCCAAGGAAGUGCCCUAAGGCGAGGUCCUUAUCCUCUUGCCAUCUGAUGGUAAUUUAACCUCAGCUUUUAAAGGGCCCUUAGGAGCAAAUAUACAAUGGGUUGUGCUUUCAGUAUUUUAAAGAGUUUAUUUUUGCCAUGCAAUGCCUAAUUGGGUAUCAUUGAAAAGAGUUGUCAAAAUAAAGUUGGUAAUUAUGUUCCUUUUAUUCCGGGGUACAUAUACUCAUUUUGUGUCUGCAUAUCUGCUGGCUUGUAUUGGUGUAGUGUGCAUCUAUGCAGAUGCUUAUACUCACAUUCCCAUGUCUGGGGUGUGUGUGUGUGUGUGUGUGUGUGUGUGUGUGAGAGAGAGAGAGAGAGGGAGAGAGGGGUUAAAAUACCCAAUGCCAGAUCAACAGAAUAAAUAAAACUUGAAUGAUAGAAACUUCAGUCACAUUAGUUUUGCCUGCAAGAAUAAAUCCCUGUAAUAUGUAAAAUAAGGGGCCAGAGGCAGAGUAAAAUUAGUCUUUUCUUGGUUACAGAUGACUGGUGUGGCAGUGACUGGCAUUGGCGUUUUGCAUGUUCUAUGUGUUAUUGUCAUUACUGUAAUUACUGAUGAUAACUAACCAUUUAUGAAGCCACAUAUUAGCUGAAUUCUGGGUAUUCUCUCAUUUAAUCCUUACAGCAAUUCUAUGUGCUGAGUAUUCUUAUUUCUCCCAUUUUACAGAUGAGGAAACUGGGGCUUCAGUUGGUUAAAUAACUUGCCCAACGUCAACAUAGCUAUUAAGUGGUGGAGCUGGGAUGCCAACCUUGCAGUGUCUGACCCCAAAGAUCAGGGUUUUAAUCAUAACACUAUUCUGCCUCUAUUUAAAAACUAACAUUUCCAUUUUCUAAGCGCAGCCCUUAAUAUAUUCAUUUAGGCAAAUUUCCAUCCUUUGCUGGCGUAAUCGCUAUUCCUUUUGUUGGUCAUUGCUCCCCUGGGCUUCCUUCAAACAUGGUCAGAGGUGCCCCAGACUUUUUAAAGAUGGAAGAAAGGCCACAUGGCCCUGCAUAAUUUGACCGAGACAGCUGUGCAGUUGGUUGUCUCAUUUAAAUUACAACCACAAAAAAGAUGUGCCAGGCUUCAUUGACACAAAGCUAAGGGCAGGAACACGGAACCGUUUCCUGAACCUGCCCUGGGUUCCUGCCAAAGGUUCUUCUUGAAAUUUUUCCUCAAAUGUAACCAAAAUUGCCUAAAGAAUGCGGGAAACCCACGUGACAUGCGGAGAUUCCAGGUCGUGGUGUCUACGACAGUCAAUGUGGAUGGCCAUGUCCUGGCAGUCUCUGAUAACAUGUUUGUCCAUAAUAAUUCCAAGCAUGGGCGGAGGGCUCGGAGGCUUGACCCCUCGGAAGGUACGCCCUCUUAUCUGGAACAUGCAGCUACUCCCUGUAUCAAAGCCAUCAGCCCGAGUGAAGGAUGGACGACGGGAGGUGCGACUGUGAUCAUCAUAGGGGACAAUUUCUUUGAUGGGUUACAGGUCAUAUUCGGUACCAUGCUGGUCUGGAGUGAGUUGAUCACUCCUCAUGCCAUCCGUGUGCAGACCCCUCCUCGGCACAUCCCUGGUGUUGUGGAAGUCACACUGUCCUACAAAUCUAAGCAGUUCUGCAAAGGAACACCAGGCAGAUUCAUUUAUACAGCGCUCAACGAACCCACCAUCGAUUAUGGUUUCCAGAGGUUACAGAAGGUCAUUCCUCGGCACCCUGGUGACCCUGAGCGUUUGCCAAAGGAAGUAAUACUCAAAAGGGCUGCGGAUCUGGUAGAAGCACUGUAUGGGAUGCCACACAACAACCAGGAAAUCAUUCUGAAGAGAGCGGCCGACAUUGCCGAGGCCCUGUACAGUGUUCCCCGCAACCACAACCAACUCCCGGCCCUUGCUAACACCUCGGUCCACGCAGGGAUGAUGGGCGUGAAUUCGUUCAGUGGACAACUGGCCGUGAAUGUCUCCGAGGCAUCACAAGCCACCAAUCAGGGUUUCACCCGCAACUCAAGCAGCGUAUCACCACACGGGUACGUGCCGAGCACCACUCCCCAGCAGACCAACUAUAACUCCGUCACCACGAGCAUGAACGGAUACGGCUCUGCCGCAAUGUCCAAUUUGGGCGGCUCCCCCACCUUCCUCAACGGCUCAGCUGCCAACUCCCCCUAUGCCAUAGUGCCAUCCAGCCCCACCAUGGCCUCCUCCACAAGCCUCCCCUCCAACUGCAGCAGCUCCUCGGGCAUCUUCUCCUUCUCACCAGCCAACAUGGUCUCAGCCGUGAAACAGAAGAGUGCUUUCGCACCAGUCGUCAGACCCCAGACCUCCCCACCUCCCACCUGCACCAGCACCAACGGGAACAGCCUGCAAGCGAUAUCUGGCAUGAUUGUUCCUCCUAUGUGAAAGAAUUGCCUUGAAGAAUUGUAUUAAUGAAGAGGUUGGAUUCUGCUACAGAGAGUAAUCUGAUACAAGUCCCAGAGUGGAACUUUUAACUCAGGCCUUUUUAAGAGGAAUCACAAUAACUGCAGAUUUUUAAACAAACAAAAUCACCGACCUUGCAAAUACUGAAAUUGGAAGAGGGAUCUGCAAGUGCAGGGUGUUGGUUAAAGUUGUACCUCCCAAGUAUUUGGGGGAUAUAUUUAUUCUGUAUUGACAAAAGCAAAUCCACUUUUUCUUUUUCUUUUUUUUUUUUAAGCUUAAUUCUGCAAUCAUUUGUCUUUUAUAAACCGUAAAGCUCUAUACAAGGGACACUAUAAAUAAGACUCCAUGUUUUAAUUUAUGAUGUUUUUAAAGCUGUGUAAAGGAAGAAUGAAGUGGUGAUAUUUACAAAAAAGUAAAAAAAAAAAAAAAGAAAAAAAGGAAAAAAAAAAAAGCUUGUAUGGGACAGAAUAGGAAUGCCAGUUAGAUUUUUUAGAAAAACUAAGGGUCGGCUUUUGCGCCUUAAAGCAUAUCAAAUGGUAGUUAGCUCAGACAGUGCAUUUUCAAUAUCUAACUUAACAUGCCACCCCUUAGCAGUGCAAGCUUAUUUAUCUCUUUUGUAUUGUUGUCUUAAGCAACUGUGUAAAUAAAUGCAGCCUGGAAAGUUAAAACGCGAUGUAAGUGAUCACAUUUUUCCCUCUACUCGAAAAUCCAGUGCCUCUAGACAGAUUGUUAAAACUGCAUAUUUAAAUCUGAUCUCAUUCUCUCCUUUUACUUAAGUCAGUUUCUUCUGAAGCCGAUGGCCUCUCGAGAGCUUGGUGGCACACAUACUGUGUGAGAAUCUCCUUUGAGACUUCAUGGAACAGGGUCCAGGCACAGAAUUCCACACUCUGCCCUCCAGUUAACAAGCCAAAACCUCACGUACGCUCCCCCAUUUGCAAGUUUAAAGUUUACUCGUCCUAAAUGCAGACUUCAUACCUAUCUUCCAAAAGUUGAUAAAAGCAACGUGGCAGGUAUUUUCGAUUUUCCCAUUCCAGAUACUGCCUCUAUCAGUCGACCCUUACCAUUUGUAACAUAAUAGAUUGAAACAACAGGUUAAGUGCUUUGGAAUUAAGAGUUAAAGGGAACCGGGGGUGGAGAAAGGAAAAGAAGGUUGAGACCUCCAAAACAUAGUUUUCUGUUCUAUGGGAAUUUUUGCUCUCAUUAUCUGGGAAGUGUUCUUAAAAAUAAGAAUUAAUAGCAAAGAUGCAGCAAAGCUCUGAGGAUGCAUUUGCCUGAUAUUUUUUUCUUUGCUCUUGUGUUUUUGUAUGUAGUUAUAAAUACUGUAGAUUUUUUUUUUGUGAUUUUUUGCCAAAGUUGUUGUUCUAUUUAUACAUUUUAAUGUCUUAAGACAUUUUUUCAAUAUCACAAAAAGAUUUUACUGCGUAUUUUGCAAAGAAAAAAAGCUCACUACCUUUAGCUUGCACAUACUUGCAAAGUUAAUUAAAAGGCUUUUUGUUUUAAAGGGGAUUUUGUAAAAUAUCCAUAUAAAUAAUGUAUUUAUCUUUCGAAUUUGUACAUUGCUUUUCCCUUCUUCCUCUUCCUUCCACCCCCAAUUUAUUUUAUUGUGUAUGUUUGCUACGUGAAAAGUGCGUAUUUGUUUGGUCACCUACACUUGUAUUAGCUGUUUCAAUGUGAUUUUUAAACAUUUCAUUUAUAGUUAUUUUUAGUAUUGUUAUAAACCAUGCUUCAGUUUUUUUAAUUUCCACCCAAAAGUCAUUGUCUAUUUUUGUAUUAUUUGUAAGUUAAGAAGUUUUUUCCAAUAUAUGGCAAAAAAAAAAAAAUAGUAGCAUAUUAUUCUUGUAGUAUUUAGUUCAGUAGAUUUAAAAAAAAAUGUAUCCUUUGCUUUGGAAGCUUACAAAACAACCCUAAUGCUGUUUUACUCUAUUAAUAUGCAUGGAAUCUCUCCCUUUGGAGUGACGCAUUUUGUGCAUUAAAUUCUAGGGAGAAACUUCAUAGAAAUCAAUGAACAUACUUUCUUUCUUAAGUCUGCUUGUAUAUUUCCUCUGUCUUUCACAUAAAUAUAAACCAGCAGAUUGGAUGCCUUAACAAUGCAAAUCAUAUUCAUUUCACUUGUACAUUGUAACUGUGCACCAGAACUGUCAGUCAUCACUAACAUUCUAAGAAAAAAGAAAAAGAAAAAAAGAAAAAAAAAAAAACAAAGAAAUCGAAAAGCACAAAAGAACUGUUUUGUUACCUUAAGACAAUGUAACUUUUUCUAGUAGAGCAAGAAAUCAUUUACAACAAUGCUGCAACUGUGCAUGCCCCCAUAUGGAUUUUGCAAUGGUUUUCACUAGGCUGUCAAGAGUGCGAUUUUUAUGGGUUGGGGUGGGUGGGGGAGGGGAGUUGUGGGAGGGUAGGGGAGGGAGGAAAGCUGUUUUUCAUGGUGAGAAAUAAUAAUGAUGACUAAUAAUAAUAAAAAAAACUGGAAAAUGUAAGCAAGGUGGACGCAUUGCUUCUCGGUACUCAGAAAGGUUAUCUGAAUUUGCGUGGUAAGCGCUGGCCUGAAGAUGUACACAAGUUAAAGCCAUAUUUUAUCUGGUGAGCCCCUUAACUGUUUCUGAAGGAAUGAACGGUCAGCCGGGAAGGUGUCCGGCUUAGACCUUGACAACAGACACUACCCAUCUGUCAGCCAUGUGCAGUGGUUAGAACUCUUCUUGAAAGUCCAAAGAGCCUUUAAAAUGUGUAUAAUUUGUGUUUUGUUGCUUCUAUUUCUAUUGAUUAGAUGAAAAGACAUUCUGGCCCUCUGAUCCUCUUUCUUCUCCACAAAAGUUUUACAAAUAAAAGAUGUUCCCCUAAAUACAGAAUAUGGCUUUAAGAAGAAAAUGAAAUGAAGAAUUAAAUUAAGAUUUCAGUGUUGGGGGAAAAAAUACAGCUUCUGGAUGACUGGAUUGCAUAACAUUGCCCUGGCCUCACAUUGUACUAGGAUGCAGCUUAAAUGAAGUCAUCUCUAAAUCUACUAACCUUUCACCUUCUUAUCAAAACUUUUUGAAUAGACACACACUGUACAGUUCAAUUGUUAGAGAACCUAACUACUGUAGAGAUUGUUAAAUUUUUUUUUUUUUUUUGCAAAAAUUCAAGCUGUAAAAACUUUUCAACUUUCACAAUAUUUAAUUAAAGUUACUUCCUGUCUGUGA